ACGCUGUUUUUCCUUUUCGUUGGCGCUUUAUAGCUACACAGUGCUAUGCCAGAGCCAGCGAAGUCUGCUCCCGCCCCGAAAAAGGGCUCCAAGAAGGCGGUGACUAAGGCGCAGAAGAAAGACGGCAAGAAGCGCAAGCGCAGCCGCAAGGAGAGCUAUUCCAUCUAUGUGUACAAGGUUCUGAAGCAGGUCCACCCUGACACCGGCAUUUCGUCCAAGGCCAUGGGCAUCAUGAAUUCGUUUGUGAACGACAUUUUCGAGCGCAUCGCAGGUGAGGCUUCCCGCCUGGCGCAUUACAACAAGCGCUCGACCAUCACCUCCAGGGAGAUCCAGACGGCCGUGCGCCUGCUGCUGCCUGGGGAGUUGGCCAAGCACGCCGUGUCCGAGGGUACUAAGGCCGUCACCAAGUACACCAGCGCUAAGUAAACAGUGAGUUGGUUGCAAACUCUCAACCCUAACGGCUCUUUUAAGAGCCACCCA